GCGAGAUCUGAAUGAGUCAAAGCCGGCGGCCUCGGCUCCUCAGCUCCACCUGACAGUAGGCCGCUGAUCGGCCGCGGGUCUUGUCGACCGCUAGGCCACCAGGUUCAUGUGGAGGCUCCCAGGCGCCCGCGCCGCGCUUCGGGUGAUCCGGACGGCGGUGGAGAAGCUGAGCCGGGCUGAAGCGGGGAGCCAGACAGCGGCGGGAGCGAUGGAGCGCGCUGUAGUGCGCUGCGUACCUUCGGAACCCAAGCUGAGCCUGUCAUUCGCUUUGGCUGAUGGUAGCCACAAGAACAUGCAGCGCGACCAGAGCGAGCCGCUGGGUCGAGUCCUCAGCCGCAUCGCUACCAAUGCCCUAAAGGGUCACGCUAAGGCGGCCGCCGCCAAGAAGAGCAGGAAGAGCCGGCCGAAUGCUAGCGGCGGUGCGGCCUGUUCAGGGCCGGGGCCUGAGCCGGCUGUGUUCUGCGAGCCCGUGGUGAAGCUGUACUACCGGGAAGAGGCAGUGGCUGAGGACGUGCUCAACGUGGAUGCCUGGCAAGACGGCGCGGUGCUGCAGAUCGGCGAUGUUAAGUACAAGGUGGAGCGCAACCCGCCCGCCUUCACCGAACUGCAGUUGCCGCGCUACAUCAUGGCCGGGUUCCCUGUGUGCCCCAAACUCAGCCUCGAAUUUGGGGAUCCCGCCAGCUCCCUUUUCCGCUGGUAUAAGGAAGCCAAGCCCGGAGCGGCGGAGCCCGAGGUCGGUGUCCCCUCGUCAUUGUCUCCCUCCUCACCUUCUUCUUCUUGGACUGAGACUGAUGUGGAGGAGCGUGUCUACACCCCGUCCAAUGCCGACAUCGGGCUAAGGCUCAAGCUUCACUGCACCCCAGGCGAUGGGCAGCGCUUUGGGCACAGCCGGGAGUUGGAAAGUGUGUGUGUGGUAGAGGCUGGGCCUGGCACCUGCACUUUUGACCACCGGCAUCUCUACACGAAGAAGGUGACUGAGGACGCUCUCAUCCGCACUGUCUCUUACAACAUCCUGGCAGACACGUACGCGCAGACUGAGUUCUCGCGAACGGUUCUGUACCCAUACUGUGCCCCCUACGCCCUGGAGCUCGACUACCGCCAGAACCUUAUCCAGAAGGAACUCACCGGCUACAACGCCGAUGUCAUCUGUUUGCAGGAGGUUGACCGCGCAGUGUUUUCUGACAGCUUGGUACCCGCCCUAGAGGCCUUCGGGCUCGAGGGGGUGUUUCGAAUCAAGCAGCACGAAGGCCUGGCCACUUUCUACCGAAAGUCUAAGUUCAGCCUUCUUAGCCAGCAUGACAUUUCAUUCUACGAAGCCCUCGAGUCCGACCCACUUCACAAAGAACUGCUGGAGAAACUAGUUUUGUACCCAUCAGCGCAGGAGAAGGUGCUCCAGAGAUCUUCUGUUCUUCAGGUUUCAGUUCUUCAGUCUACAAAGGACUCUUCUAAAAGGAUAUGUGUUGCUAAUACCCAUCUUUACUGGCAUCCUAAAGGUGGGUAUAUUCGCCUCAUUCAAAUGGCAGUAGCCUUGGCUCACAUAAGACAUGUUUCAUGUGAUCUGUAUCCUGGCAUACCAGUUAUAUUUUGUGGGGACUUUAAUAGUACACCAUCAACAGGAAUGUAUCAUUUUGUCAUCAAUGGCAGCAUUCCAGAGGAUCAUGAAGACUGGGCUUCCAAUGGGGAGGAGGAAAGAUGCAAUAUGUCUCUUACACAUUUCUUCAAGCUGAAAAGUGCUUGUGGUGAACCUGCUUACACAAAUUAUGUUGGUGGCUUUCAUGGAUGUCUAGAUUACAUUUUCAUUGACUUAAAUGCUUUAGAGGUUGAACAGGUGAUUCCAUUACCUAGUCAUGAAGAAGUUACCACCCACCAGGCCUUACCUAGUGUUUCCCAUCCCUCUGAUCACAUAGCACUUGUAUGUGAUUUAAAAUGGAAAUAGAUGUGUGUUUAAUGGAAUUGAAGUCUGAAAAGGAAGUAGUUAUUUUAGCAGAAAAUUUAAUAUGAAUCAAAGCUUAUAUGUAAACUUCAAGGAGGAAUGGUAAAAUGUUCAGCCCUCCUAGUUAUGUUCCUGAUGUCUUCGUUAUGAAACUGUUGAUGUUUGCAUCAUACAUCUUCUCUUUCCUUGUUUUCCUCUACAAUUGGAGGAGAAACAAAUAUAUUUCUUACUAGCAAAAUAGAAAAUUGAAUUAUUUUUCUCCAAAUUGAGACUCUCAGAAAAGGAAGAUUGAAUUAGCGUGUUUUUUGUUUGUUUGUUUUUGUUUUUGUUUUUGUUUUUUUGAGAUGGAGUUUCACUCUUGUUGCCCAGGCUGGAGUGCAAUGGCACAAUCUCGGCUCACUGCAACCUCCGCCCCCUGGGUUUAAGCGAUUCUCCUGCCUCAGCUUCCCGAGUAGCUGGGAUUACAGGCGUGCGCCAACAUGUCUGGCUAAUUUUUGUAUUUUUAGUAGAAAUGGGGUUUCGCCACGUUGGCCAGGCUGGUCUUGAACUCCUGACCUCAGGUGAUCCACCCACCUCGGCCUCCCAAAGUGUUGGGAUUACAGGCGUGAGCCACCGCACCCGGCCCUUGUGUACAUUUUUAUAAGAGAAUUUUUUUAGCUAGGAGUUCAGAAUUUUUAAAGUACCAUUUGAAUGAUCUUAAUUUUUCUUUCAUGACAACACAUUCCAAAAUGAAUCAUGCUUAUGUACUAAGAGGGAAAAUGUAUUUAAGUUAAGGGUGAGAGACUUAAGUUAUAGGUGACCUUAGAGACCUAAGGUGAGAGACUUGACACAUGGAAGGAGUAACAUUAGGGUCUACCUCUACCUCAAUUUAGUUAGCGAUUUACUACAAUUUCAGAGCUUUAACAAAAGAUAAAAAUAAAUCGUCACCAAUUGUUAUUGCUUCUCAUCUUUCAUUUUUCAAUGAACAAGUAAGGUAUUUUCAUUCUUAUUUUUAGGAUUUUAGUUUUUAGUGUAUGGUACAAAUGAACACAGUUUAUAUUCUAAUUCUUACUGCAGCUCAUUUUAAUUUUUAGGAUGCAAGCACAAUUUAGUAUUCAAAGUGAGUAGCAACAUAUUCAACUUGAUCCCAUUGUCUUCAGUUACUCUUGCCCAUGAAAAAUGUUCAUAAAUGAACAGGGUAUUUGACCAUAUGAUAUUAGAAAAUACAGCACAUUACUUUAUGAGAAACUACCUACUGAUAUGGGCUUGAAAUUUUGGAUGAAUCAUUGAGCAUUUCUACACUAGAAGUAAUUUCAAAAUUGUUGGUUUUUAUAAACAGGAAAAAGGUUGAGUAGUGGGACUUUUAAGCAUCUCUGAAAUAAAAAACUUCUUUUUACAGACAAGCAUUAUAGUUUGAGUUACAGACAACAGUGUGUAUAUAUGUAAUAUAUAUAUAGUAAAAUGAAAUUUAAAUAUGAAGCCAAACUUUUUAAAAUUAGAAACUACAAAUGGUUAUACUGAUUAGUGUCUAGCCUAGAGUGGUAACCAUGCUUUACUAAUUCAGUUAUGAAAUACAUUAUUUAUAAUGCAUUAGCUGUAUUAGCUGUUGCUUUUUUGAUGUUCAGGAUAACUAUGUUAUCUCAUUUCUGCAUUUAAUUAAUAGCUCGAGUAUUAAAAGCCCACUCCCUUCAAGAAAAGCUUUGAUUUUCCCCAGUCAUGAAAGCCCUUGUUUCAAAUUCUUUAAUCUCUGAACCUAGUAUCAUAAGAAUUUCCUCUUUUGAUAACAUCUGUACUUUCAUAUUCUGCUCACUAUCAAAUGUAUUGUUAACACUUAGUAAGUUUGAAAAUGAAGGGGUUUUAUCUGCAUUUGACAUUGAACCUUGAAGUACUUUAAGUACUCCAAGGGGAAAAUUAAAGUGGAAGUUUCUUCGGAUCUUGUUUAGAAAAAACUAUAAAUAAAAAAUUGAUGCUACCAAAUUGUGCCUUCCUAAAUAACAUUUUUGAGAGCAUUUUAACAGCAGUUUACAAAUAUGUAAAUAAUAGAUUAAAACCAAAUCUUGAUUCUCUUGUGAAUUUUUUUUUCAUUUUAAAAAUAUGUUUUUGGGCUGUUUUCAAAGAAAGAUGUUGAUAGAACCCUUAGAGUGACUUGGGAGAAAACAAAGUGUCACAUCAAAAAGUUGAGAAACAUUUUGAAAGAAAAAAUUCGAACAUGCCCAUGAAAAAAGCAUACAGCUUCCACAUUAACACUGGCUAGAUUAAACUCUAGUCAGAAAAACUCAGCACUUAACAGACAUUCCAUGUCCUAUAUCCUUAAUUUUGAUGUUUUCUGACUAAACAAUAUACUCAGAUUGUAUACAGGCAUUUCACAUUAUUAGGACAUGGAAUGUUAUUGUGAAGUGCCAUAUACUGUGAUCAAAUCUCCAGUAUACGGAUACGUUAAAAUGAUUGGAGUCCAAAGGUAGGGAACACUAAGAAAAUGUAUAAAUAGCAUACACAUUUCUUUGUACUCAUGAGUUAGAAUGCAGUGUUAUUCAGAAAUGUCUGUUUAAAGCACCUAUGUGAUUGCAUUUUUCUAUUACAUUUGGAUUUUUUAGUACAUUUAAUUUUAAGAAAACAUGGGAAAUCUAGCGACUUUCUAUGGUAAACCACAUUUUAUAAUGUCACAAGUUCUUGCUAUAGGAAUUAACAUUCUAGAAUUUUAUAUUGAUUAUAAAAGAGUAUUUCAGAACAUAUUAUUCUGUUAAAAUGAACUCUUGCACAGUUGCCGCUACAGCAAAUGUGUCUGCCAAUAAUCAAAAUUCAUGAGCAAACAAUCGUUUCUGGCUGUAAUGUAUGUUCUUUUUGAAAUUCUGUAUGCUAAAAUCAGUUGUUUCAAAAUUUCAAGAAUUCCACUGAGUAGUGAUUUUUCUGAGUACUAAGCUAUGAUCUCAUCAGAAUGUGCUGGUUUCAGUCUGGAGAUAGAUUUCUGAGGAGCCUAAUACAAGGGAGAGAAUGUCCAAAGAACACUACUGUGGAAAGUUCUUACGAUGGAAAUUGACAUCUUUUGUAUCUCAUUCUCCAGCCGUGAAAUAAAGGCAGAGGUUCCCUGCAAACUAGUUUGGUUGGGAUAAAUCCAAUAUUUAUAUAUAAUGAAAAAUAAAAGUUUGCAUUAUUAGUUUAUCACAAGACCCAUGUGACAACUCAGAAAAUAUUCUCAGCAUAAUUUUUUUAAGAGAUAGAGUCUCACUGUUACCCAGGCUGGAGUGCAGUGGUGCAGUCAUAACUUACUACAGCCUCAAACUGCGGGGCUCAAAUGAUCCUCCUGCCUCAGCGUCCCAAGUAGUUGAGAUUACAAGCCCAACCUUCCAUAACUGAAAACUAACUUUCUUUUUUUCUUUUUUUAUUAUUAUACUUUAAGUUCUAGUGUACAUGUGCCCAACGUGCAGAUUUGUUACAUAGGUAUACAUGUGCCAUGUUGGUUUGCUGCACCCGUUAACUCGUCAUUUACAUUAGGUAUUUCUCCUAAUGCUAUCCCUCCCCCAGCCCUGAAAAUGAAUUUUUUAAACACAAAUAAAAAAUAUUUCAGUGUUUUGAGAAUUUUAAUAAUUUGCUUAAUAUAGUACAGGAAGGCAACACUAUCUAGAGGGCCAGGCAUAGUGGCUCUUGACUGUAAUCACAACAUUUUGGGAGGCUGAGGCAGGAGGAUCACUUGAGCUGAGGAGUUCAAGACCAGCCUUGGCAACAUUGUGAGACCCUAUCUCUGCAAAAAAUAAAAUUAACCAGGCAUGGUGGUGCAUGCCUGUAGUCCCAGCUGCUCAGGAGGCUGAGGCCAGAGGAUCACUUGAGCCCAUGAGGUCAAGCCUGCAGUGAGUUGUGAUCAAGGUGCGCUGCACUCCAGCCUGGGUAAUAGAGCAAGACCCUGUCUUCAAAAAACCACUCUAGAUUUCAUGUUGUAGGGGGUAGGGAGGACAAUUUUUAACAGCUUUAACUGACAUGGGUAAUAUAUAAGUUCUGUGUUCUCACUUUAUAUGAAAGUACUUUUUUAAAUGUUAAAAAUACUAGAGCUGUAUUAACUUCGUGAUUUUAUUUUUCUUCUUAGCACUAACUUCAAAAUAACCAUACAGUACUGCUUGUAAUUUUUGUAUUUUUAGUAGAGACAGGGUUUCACCAUAUUGGCCAGGCUGGUCUUGAACUCCUGAACUCAAGUGAUCUGCCUGCCUCAGCCUCUGAAAGUGCUGGGAUUACAGGCAUGAGCCACGGUACCCGGCCUAAAUUUUAAUUUUAUAUAUAAAUGGCAAAAUAAUCUUAAAUAUAGUAAAUCUGUUCACCUAUCUGCUAUGCUAGCAAAUUCUGGGUUGUCAAAAAUCCAUGUUCAUACUGUCAGUGUUAGAUUUUUACUCAUAAUUUAAAAUUUCCCCGCAAAAUUUCACAGAAAACUGAAUUAUUCAUCUCUAUCUUCUGUCCAAUUUAUGUAAUGAAUGUAUGUCAAAGCAUUUAUAUAACACAGUCCAUUUUGCCCAGUAAUUCACUUUAAUGAUGUUAUCAUGAAGUAUUGAUGUACUUUUUUUUUAGUGUAUUGAAGUAUUCCUAGGUUGCAUUUGUGCUAGUUUCAUACCAUUUGUGUUCCUUAUAUAUUGAAGAUGGUUCAGUAGGGGAAAUGGAUAGGCUUUAUUUAGUUGGCUUUCUUAUACUGGAUAAUAUAAACACUUUUUUUUUCUUUUUUGAGACAGGGUCUGGCUUUGUCACCCAGGCUUGGAGGGCACUGGUGCCAUCACGGCUUACUGCAACCUCCACCUCCUGGGCUUAUGCAAUCCUCCCACCACAGCCUCCCCAAAUAGCUGGGACUACAGGUGCGCACCGCCACACCUGGCUAAUUUUUGUAUAUUUUAUAGGCAAAAAAAAAAAAAAAAAUGGUUUCACCAUGUUGCCCAGGCUGGUCUUGAAAUUCUCAGUUCAAGCAGUCCACCCACCUCGGCCUCCCAAAGUGCUGAUAUUACAGACAUGAGCCACCCCACCCAGUCAGCACACAUUUUUUUUUUUUUUAAAUAAGACAGGGUGUUGCUGUUGCCCAGGCUGGAGCGCAGUGGCAUGAUCAUAGCUCACUGCAGCAUCAAACUCCAGGGCUUAAGCGAUCCUCCCACCUCAGCCUCCUGAGUAGCUGGGACUAUAGGUGCAUGCCACCAUGCCUGGCUAAUUUUUUAAAUUGUUUGUAGAGAUGGGGGUCUCUCUAUGUUGCCCAGACUGGUCUUAAACUCCUGGGCUCAAAUGACUCUCCCGCUUCAGCCUCCCAAAGUACUGGGAUUAUAGGUGUGAGCCAGCACACAUAGCCCUUUUUUUAAAAAAAUUAAAAACAAAUUUUUUCUCCAGAAAAAAACAUAUUUAUCAACUUUUAAAAACAUUUUAUGGGUACAUAGUAGGUGUAUAUAUUUAUGUGGGACAUAUUUCUUUUGAUAGAGUAAAUUGAGUAUUCAUCACAUCAAGCAUUCAUUUGUGUUACGAACAUUCCAAUUGUACUCUCUCAGUUAUUCUAAAAUGUGAUAUACACACUUUUAAAAGGAUUUAUUGCGCUGGGCGCGGUGGCUCACGCCUGUAAUCCCAGCACUCUGGGAGGCUGAGGCCGGUGGAUCAUGAGGUCAGAUCGAGACCAUCCUGGCCAACAUGGUGAAACCCUGUCUCUACUAAAAAUACAAAAAUUAGCUGGGCAUGGUGGCGCGCGCCUGUAGUCUCAGCUGCUUGGGGAGGCUGAGGCAGGAGAAUCACUUGAACCCGGGAGGCAGAGGUUGCAGUGAGCCGAGAUCACGCCAUUGCACUCCAGCCUGGCAACAAAGCGGGACUCUGUCUCAAAAAUAAAAUAAAAUAAAAUUUUAAAAAAAGGAUUUAUUGCAUAUAAUUCUUAUAUCCCCUGUGGAAUAGUUUGGAGAAAUGGUACAUCCAAAGAUAAAAUCAGUUAGAAAUAAACAGUGGCCUUCCUCAGAAAAGCUGGGCUAUAGUGUUUUGGGUAUCUUAAACCAAGAAAGGGUAUUUCUAUCCCAGCUGUAGAGUUUUUAAUAAUUCUAUUAUAAAUAAUGGAAUCAGGCCAGCACAGUGGCUCACGUCACAUAAUCCCACUCUCCUUAAGAGCUUUUUUUGUCACUGCAUAUCAACUCAGUUGACAAGGACUGGCCCCCAAAAGAAGCUGCAUACUCACUUGGCAGUCACUCCCCAUUCUCCCUAGCUCCUGGCAACAACUUAACCUGUCUCUGUGGAUUUGCCUAUUCUGGACAUUUCAUAUAAAUUGAAUCAUAAUUUAUGUAGUCUUUUGUGACUGGCUUCUUUUACUUAGGAUGUUUUUAAGGUUCUUACUGUUGUAGGAUGUAUCAGGAGUUUGUUUUUAUGAUGAAUGUUCCAUCUUAUGGACGUACCACAUUUGUCCAUUCAUUAGUUGACAGACAUUUGAAUUGCUUCCACUUCCUGGCUUCUAUGAAUAAUGCUGCCAUAAACAUUUGUGAUAAGUUUUUGAGUGAAUAUGUGUUUUUGUUUCUCUUGGGCACAUACAGGGAAUGGAAUUGUUGGGUGCUGUGAUAACCUUUUGAGGAACUGCCAGACUUACGGAAAGCAGUUGCACUAUUUUGCAUUCCCACCAAGCAAUAUGAGGGUUCCAGUUUCCCUCCAUCCUCAUUAACACUUUAUUAUCUUUUUGAUUAUAGGCAUCCUAGUGUCAAGUGGCAUCUUAUUGUGGUUUUGAUUUGCAUUUCCAUGAUGGUUAACGAUGUUAAGCAUCUUUUCAUGUGCUCGUUGGCCAUCUAUAUAUCUCUGGAGAAAUGUCUUUUGAAAUACUUUGCCCAUUUAAAAAUGUUAUUUGUUGUUUAGCCACCCCUCCUUAAAAAAUAAAUAAUAUAAUAAUCCAUCA